AGCCGCGGCGACUGUGUUUGCACCCGGCGGACCAUGCCAGGACUACGGACCCGGACAGGACUGAUGGCCUCAGAGAGGCAAGUAUUCAAGGGGCACUUCACAAACAGCUUCCUCAAACCCCACCCCCUCCCCCGCACUGCGCUGCUACUUGCACUGCGGCUCCUGGGGGGAAGCAAAGUACCGGCAGCUGGGUGGUGAGGGGCUUUCUUCCAGAAAGAAACGGAGAGCAAGUGGUCUUCCUCCCUAGCCGCGGCGACCCAUGCCAGGUAAAAAUCCCAGCCGAGGUCCCCGGUCCCGUCCCCUCCUCCAGGUCAAGGGCUCGGGACUGGAGAAGCAGCCAACUGGAGCUGAUAUUCGGGAAGCUAAGCCUGAGGCUGCUCUGGAGGGCCGGAGAAGCGAGCGGCCAGGCUUGGCACCCGCCAAAUGUGCCUUGCCAAAAUGAAGAGGAAGGAAGGCGACUCCGGAGCCCAGCAGAUCUGAGCGCCAGGCUGGCCAGCACCCAGAGAGCCCAGAGCCGCAGGAAAAAAUGUGAAAAGUACCAGGAGACCACUGGGUAAUCGCCCCAGUGCAAAGGGCCUUUCUUCCUACCCACCGCAAUUGCAGCAAAUAACUCCAGGGAGGGGAAUCAGAGGCGCCGGGGAUUGCGCCCUGGGAGAGCCCUAUCUGCUGAAAGAGAGCGCCUAAUGCCGUUACUUCCCAGUGUAGCCUUUCCACUCGGCAGACCAAGCGCCUCUCCUUCGAGUCGCUACCCGCUUGGAGUCGGCUCAGAAUCAGGCUGCUAAAGGUCCCUGGAGCCCCUCCCCCAGCGAAUCCGAGCCUGCAGCUUCAGCACCAGAGGCUGGACAGCGCCCCGGCCCUAGGGUGCCCAUGGUCGGUGCCUGCGCACGGCUCGGCCUCCCAGCCCACGCCACUUGCGCUCGCGGCCCCUCAGACCCCACGCGGAGGAGGUCAGGAGGUGACACAGGUUCGCGGAAGAAAGCGGGACUCAUCUUCCUCAUUUCUCCAGGGAUUUAGGUGUGGGAUUCUAGGAGAGCAUUCUCUCUCGCUCUGGCCACGACCAGUGGAAAAACUUGGCGCCAAAUUUAGGCAGUGGUGCGGGGAGCAGAGGCACGAUUGCAGGCGGUGAGCAAAGGGGCAAGCGGGACAGAGGAUCUACUGUGAGCCCCAGGCUCUGGUGUUCCGUGAAAAAUCGCCACAUUUAAAUCCUGCGCUCCCCCGUGCUCCCUCUCGCUCUCUCCCCCUUCCUUUUUCCCUUCCUUCCUUCCUCCCCGCGCUCUCUGUAUGCCUUAAUAGGAGUGAGUGAAAGGGAAAGAGUGGGGUGGAGGGAGAAGAUAUUGAAGCCGAGGUAAGAAGCACAUUUUAUCUAGGUCUCAAAACUCAAGCGUGGAUGAAAUCUGUUCAAAAAGAACAUCAAGGUACGCGUUUUUUUACCCAAAGGAGCCCAAAGUGACCUUUGUAUGAGGAGCAAAGAUUAUUGUUUGGCCAAGAAGGGGAAAGAUAGCGGAGGGAGAGGCGCUAUCACAAAAGGGCUAACGGAGGUGGAGAAGGAAGGGAAAGGACUUGGCACUAGCAUGCUUACCAGGCAACCAGUCGCAGCACCUGCCUCCUGUUGCCUUGGUUACGGUGGGUGGCGGGGCUUUGGCCACUGAUAAUCAGUGAGCACCUUGACUAUUUAAAAUAUCUCCUGGGGAGCCCCUGCCUUGUCUGGGCUAGGUGAGAGGCACAUCGAUCCCGCGUAAGGCCCCGUCUGGGGAAAUCCUGGAAGAUGUUUGUUUUUUGUUUGUUUGUUUUUAUUUUAAGUAAAGGCGCAUAGCAGAGCAACUUACCUUUCCACCACUACAGUCAUCCCCUCCCCCCUCCACCCCAUGGCUUCAUUUCUCCAGGAUUUACAAUUUGGGCUUUUAUAUUUUUCAUUUAGUCCUUUAUACUGAAGGAGCUGAGUUCCUAUCCCCACCCUCUCUUUUUCCCCCUUAAAAUGAGAAAAAAAAAUUGCUUUUCCUGGAUGUACAGGAGGGAGACAAGGAAAUUGUCCAGGGGUGUCUACUGUAGAGAGAAACUUUCUCCCUGGUUUGAUAGUCAUCCCUGCCCCACUAAACCACUCCCCUCAGGGGAGAGAGGGCUGAAUUCUGGAUUACCCCCACUUCUCACCUUGCCCCAUAGACCACAUAGAAAGCACAGGUAGAGGGAAACGUGUCUCCCUUAGCAGAUGGACACUAGCAUCACUCUCAUUUGAUUCCUCAAGAUUCUCUUCUCUUCUUCCUCCCCAGCAUCGCCUUCAUAAUUAGCAAAUACAGCACCUAAAGCUUCUAAUCCUCUGAGUUUUUCUGUUUCCCUUGAUUGACAAACAUUGACUCCACUUUCACCUGUCAGCCUUGCCCUGCCUAUGUCCAUUAGAAACAUCUGGGUAGGAAAUUAUUUUACUCAUAAUUUUCCAAAGGCAGCUGUAACAUUCUCAGAAUGAUUUGAGAGGAAAUCGCUAGCAAGUUACCAGAACAGCCUGUGCUCUGUGCACUGUUUCAUCUCAAAUAAGUCUAAGUGCCAUGAACGUUCUCUUUCCCGAAAAACAGCAACAAUAACAACAACAAAAAGAAGUUUGUUUUAAACUGAGAUAUUACUUGACAACACGGGGUUGGAGAACAUUUCUGUUUCAGGCAGGAACUGUGAUAUCUUUAUCUGUGAUGCCCUGAACCAUAAACACACAGGUCUUUUCUUUUCUCCUCUUGUUCUCUUCUUUUCUCUCCAUUUCCUUCAUUUAUUAUUAAUAUAAGAAUUUUUAUUCAUUAUAAUUUCAGCAUAAGUUUAAAAGGUCAAAAAUUCGCUCGGUGAACUGACUUGAUAGUUUUGCGGGUAUUUACAUUAAAAUGCUUUUAAAAUGCUUUUCUCUCCCAUGUUACUAUAGAAACUUCCCUUUAGACCAGACCAGACAGCUGGUCUGCUUUUUGUACUUUUCUUCCCAAAGAAGUGCUUUCCUUUAUGAAUUGUCCGGGGCAGCUAUCAUUGAUCACAUCAGUAAUGUCCCAUAGCAACAGUUGUGUGGUUUUUUUUAAUUAUUAUUCACUUUCUGCUUAUUUUCUUUAUGGACAAAGGGUCUACUUUCAAGAAGAUAACUGAGCUCUUAUUGGCUGGAAAGGAAGAAGCAUUCUUUCAUUGGUUGGUGUGUAUUGCCUUGUCAACCAAUAAGAGGAUGCCAUUUAUCCUUUUCUGACUAGCUGAGUGAGCAGGGUACACAGAAGGAUUGAAUCUGCCUUAGUUCCAUCCAGUAGCAAAGGACAGAACUCAGAGUCCUGGACUCAGGAUCUGGAAUUGACUUUGGCUAAUCCAGAUUGCACUGACUUGCAAGGAUGACAUUUUUUACCUACCUAUUCGCAGCUUACUUCAACAUACCUGCCUUAUACAUUGUCCUAUGGCUUUUUUCCCCCUUCAUUUUAGGAGAUACUGUGAUCAUCUUUCCAAGUCAGUGCAGGUUAUUGUUACCAGCACACUGAGGGUCCAGAGAAUUUUGUGAUUUCCCCUAAAAAUAGAUAAUUGGUCCUCAUUAUUAGAGAUUUGGUGAAAACUUUUGGAGAUGAAGAUGGAAAGCUAGAAGUCGGAAGAACUGCAUUGCUUGUGAUGCAGAAUGGAUAUCUCAGCUUGUGGAUUCACUCUACUCAGCUCUCAGCUUUGGUGUUUUGUGUUUGGUGUUUGGUGUCCUCUUCACUUUGAUUUUUAUUUGUCUGUUUUUCCACUUUCAUUCUUCAGAGCUGCGCUUUUGGCCUGAAUUUUCAGUGACAAAUAGAAAAGCUGAAUGGAUGGAGACAAUGACUCUUUAAUUCAAUGUAAGAGCUGACUCAUCGCUUCCCAGGAAGACUUGUUGCAGGCUGCUGCCCCAUUGGAAGAUUACUCCCCAGGCUUCCCUUGCCCCAAGCAGUGAGCUGACUGGAAUGGUACCCCGGGAGGCCCCUGAGUCUGCUCAGUGCCUGUGCCCUUCCCUCACCAUCCCAAAUGCCAAGGAUGUGCUUCGGAAGAGGCACAAGAGAAGGAGCCGACAGCACCAGCGGUUCAUGGCCCGGAAGGCCUUGCUGCAGGAGCAGGGGCUGCUGAGCAUGCCUCCAGAACCAGGGUCCUCCCCACUGCCCACCCCUUUCGGGGCAGCGACAGCAACUGAAGCUGCCAGCAGUGGGAAGCAGUGUCUGAGGGCUGGAUCUGGCAGUGCCCCAUGCAGCAGAAGGCCUGCUCCCGGGAAAGCCUCAGGGCCCUUGCCCAGCAAGUGUGUGGCUAUCGACUGUGAGAUGGUGGGCACGGGACCCCGAGGGCGGGUAAGCGAGCUGGCCCGCUGUUCCAUUGUGAGCUACCAUGGCAAUGUCCUCUAUGACAAGUACAUCAGGCCUGAGAUGCCCAUCGCUGACUACCGUACCCGCUGGAGUGGCAUCACUCGGCAGCACAUGCGCAAGGCUGUCCCCUUCCAGGUGGCCCAGAAAGAGAUCCUUAAGCUCCUGAAGGGCAAGGUGGUGGUGGGGCACGCGCUGCACAACGACUUCCAGGCGCUCAAGUAUGUCCACCCUCGGAGCCAGACCCGGGAUACGACCUAUGUCCCAAACUUCCUCAGCGAGCCCGGCCUCCACACCCGGGCCCGGGUCUCUCUAAAGGACCUGGCCCUGCAGCUGCUGCACAAGAAGAUCCAGGUGGGCCAGCACGGGCACUCAUCAGUAGAAGAUGCCACGACAGCCAUGGAGCUCUACCGGCUGGUGGAGGUGCAGUGGGAACAGCAGGAGGCCCGCAGCCUCUGGACCUGCCCCGAGGACAGAGAACCUGACAGCAGCACAGACAUGGAACAGUACAUGGAGGACCAGUACUGGCCCGAUGACCUGGCCCACGGCAGCAGAGGAGGAGCCAGGGAGGCACAGGACAGAAGGAAUUGAGAAGGGGGCGGGGCUCCCUGGCUGGGCUUCCGGUGUGGCCGGUAGGAAGUGGGGGCCAGGAGAGCAGCGGGCACUCCUUCCUGGGCAGGGUGGGGCAGGAUGCAGUGAGCCAGCCCCAGGGCCAGAGGAGUAGGGGUCAUCUGUUACCUUGACACCCUCUGCACACAGCAUAGCCCUCUCUCUCUCCAGGGCUGUUGGUUCUUUCUUCUGACUCCUGUGGUUUUGCUAAUGGCACUUUACAGACUCCAUGGAGAUGUCAGGUGGACCAUCUUCUAGGGCCCAGCAGGAGUAGGGAAUGUGCCAACAGACUGCCCAGGUUGCCGUGGCCUUCCCCACCCCCCAGAUCUCCUGAGUCAUCAUGCUGUGCUAAUGAAAGGGAUCAUAUCAUCCUCUCUGGGGAUGGUGGGUGGGGGUGUCAAUAUCCUGGAGCUCCCUUACCCCAACUCAAUGACUUGGGGGUAAAGUUCUCUUCCUUUUGUUGCCUACCUCUUCCUCCACUCAUUUGGGUUCAGAAUAAACAUGUCCUGAAGUUAAAGAGGAGUUAAGUCCUAAAGGAGGCAUUUCUUCCCCACCUCCCUGACCUGGAACUCUGGCUACAGCCAUUGUAGGAACUCCGUGCCUGGCCUGUCAGCUCCCUGCUAGGCUACAGUGGAAUAGCAGAGCCCACAGGCUUCUCGUGGGGAGUUGGCUCCUUAACAUUUCUUGGCAACAGAAAGCCCCAGGCACAGCUCAGGGAGGAGGGAAGGCAGGUAAGCUUUGGACGAGAACUGGCAUAUUUAUUUUGACCCAAAUCAGGGAUUUCCCCAGUCCACCCAGUACUGGGCUCUUAAGCAAAAGUCUGAGAAACAAGACAGUGGUUUGAAUUCUGGGGCCUUUGUGUAGGAUUGUGCCUGACCUUUAUUUAUUUAUUAACAGCAGGGCCACUCGUCUAGGGCAGUGGAGUCUGCGUGUCUCCUGGGGCUGGGGCAGGGCAUUGGCAGUUACGCAGUGGCCCUGAACCUGGUCUGGUGCCCCCGAACCUGGUCUGAUGCCCCCUCAGCUCUUUGACAAUCACUGUGGCUGUUGGGUUUUCUCCUAUUUCUAAAAAUGUUCUCUUCUUUCCUAAGUGACAGUUUUGAAGUAUUGGAUAACCAAGAGCUCAGGUCACACAGACCUUGGAGCCCCAUCUUUGCUUGCAGCUUAGCUUUGAGAUACUAAGCAAGCGAGGGACUUCACUCUUGAGGCUGUUUUUUCCUCAUCUGUAAAGUGGGGAUAGUGGUACGGCCUACCUCAUAGGGUUGUAAUGAGCACUAAAUGUGAAGUGCUUGGCACAGUGCCUGGCACAUGGUGAGCCACAGCUACUGUGAGUUUCUGUUUAUCCCCCUUUUUUUUUUUUAAGCCCAUUGUUUAUUCUUUGAGAAUUUGUUGUAACUUCUUCAGGAUAACACCUGAGUCCACAGGCUGAGCAGCUGUGGCCCAGACAGAACUGCUCCGGCUUGGCUGUUCCAGCAGGUGGGGCGCUGGCCUCGGUGAGGGCACAGCAGCAAGGUUCACGGAUAUCCGUGUGUCUUGUCUGUGGCCACCAGGCACAGGUUUGGCUUCCGGUCAGUGUCCCGACACUGUGCGGGAGGUGACAACAGAGCAAAGCAGCGCAGGGGUCAGGGAGGUACAGACACUGCUGAAAUCACACUACCCCACCCUCAGCUGAAGCCCCACGUUCCACAAACUUGGGGUCAUAGAUUGUCCAGUCACUGGCUCCCUCCCUGUCAGCACAGCACAGAGGAAGGGGCUAACUGAAUCUUUUACCACUUCUGGCCUGGCUCCAGAACUUUGUUCUAGAUUCCUUAAAAGUCGGUAGCUGAUGUCAAACUCAAUUGAGCAGUAGCUUUGAUCCCUUGGUCUGGGGGUCGAAGGAAGAUGGUGCUGUUAUCAGCGGGGAAAUGUACUAUUUAAGAUCAGCUUUGUUGUAAAACCAUUUGUUCUAGAAUAAAACUCAAUUGGAAACGUG